GCAUGCGCUCGCAUCAUGGCGGCUGAGUGGGCUUCUCGUUUCUGGCUUUGGGCUACGCUGCUGAUUCCUGCGGCCGCGGUCUACGAAGACCAAGUGGGCAAGUUUGAUUGGAGACAGCAAUAUGUUGGGAAGGUCAAGUUUGCCUCCUUGGAAUUUUCCCCUGGAUCCAAGAAGUUGGUUGUAGCCACAGAGAAGAAUGUGAUUGCAGCAUUAAAUUCCCGAACUGGGGAGAUCUUGUGGCGCCAUGUUGACAAGGGCACGGCAGAAGGGGCUGUGGAUGCCAUGCUGCUGCACGGACAGGAUGUGAUCACUGUGUCCAAUGGAGGCCGAAUCAUGCGUUCCUGGGAGACUAACAUCGGGGGCCUGAACUGGGAGAUAACCCUGGACAGUGGCAGUUUCCAGGCACUUGGGCUGGUUGGCCUGCAGGAGUCUGUAAGGUACAUCGCAGUCCUGAAGAAGACUACACUUGCCCUCCAUCACCUCUCCAGUGGGCACCUCAAGUGGGUGGAACAUCUCCCAGAAAGUGACAGCAUCCACUACCAGAUGGUGUAUUCUUACGGCUCUGGGGUGGUGUGGGCCCUCGGAGUUGUUCCCUUCAGCCAUGUGAACAUUGUCAAGUUUAAUGUGGAAGAUGGAGAGAUUGUUCAGCAGGUUAGGGUUUCAACUCCGUGGCUGCAGCACCUGUCUGGAGCCUGUGGUGUGGUGGAUGAGGCUGUCCUGGUGUGUCCUGACCCGAGCUCACGUUCCCUCCAAACUUUGGCUCUGGAGACGGAAUGGGAGUUGAGACAGAUCCCACUGCAGUCUCUCGACUUAGAAUUUGGAAGUGGAUUCCAACCCCGGGUCCUGCCUACCCAGCCCAACCCAGUGGACGCUUCCCGGGCCCAGUUCUUCCUGCACUUGUCCCCAAGCCACUAUGCUCUGCUGCAGUACCAUUAUGGAACGCUGAGUUUGCUUAAAAACUUCCCACAGACUGCCCUAGUGAGCUUUGCCACCACUGGGGAGAAGACGGUGGCUGCAGUCAUGGCCUGUCGGAAUGAAGUGCAGAAAAGUAGCAGUUCUGAAGAUGGGUCAAUGGGGAGCUUUUCGGAGAAGUCUAGUUCAAAGGACUCUCUGGCUUGCUUCAAUCAGACCUACACCAUUAACCUAUACCUCGUGGAGACAGGUCGGCGGCUGCUGGACACCACGAUAACAUUUAGCCUGGAACAGAGCGGCACUCGGCCUGAGCGGCUGUAUAUCCAGGUGUUCUUGAAGAAGGAUGACUCAGUGGGCUACCGGGCUUUGGUGCAGACAGAGGAUCAUCUGCUACUUUUCCUGCAGCAGUUGGCAGGGAAGGUGGUGCUGUGGAGCCGUGAGGAGUCCCUGGCAGAAGUGGUGUGCCUAGAGAUGGUGGACCUCCCCCUGACUGGGGCACAGGCCGAGCUGGAAGGAGAAUUUGGCAAAAAGGCAGCAAUUCAAGAUGGCUUGCUGGGGAUGUUCCUGAAACGCCUCUCGUCUCAGCUUAUCCUGCUGCAAGCAUGGACUUCCCACCUCUGGAAAAUGUUUUAUGAUGCUCGGAAGCCCCGGAGUCAGAUUAAGAAUGAGAUCAACAUUGACACCCUGGCCAGAGAUGAAUUCAACCUCCAGAAGAUGAUGGUGAUGGUAACAGCCUCAGGCAAGCUUUUUGGCAUUGAGAGCAGCUCUGGCACCAUCCUGUGGAAACAGUAUCUACCCAAUGUCAAGCCAGACUCCUCCUUUAAACUGAUGGUCCAGAGAACUACUGCUCAUUUCCCCCAUCCCCCACAGUGCACCCUGCUGGUGAAGGACAAGGAGUCGGGAAUGAGUUCUCUGUAUGUCUUCAAUCCCAUUUUUGGGAAGUGGAGUCAGGUAGCUCCCCCAGUGCUGAAGCGCCCCAUCUUGCAGUCCUUGCUUCUCCCAGUCAUGGAUCAAGACUACGCCAAGGUGUUGCUGUUGAUAGAUGAUGAAUACAAGGUCACAGCUUUUCCAGCCACUCGGAAUGUCUUGCGACAGCUACAUGAGCUUGCCCCUUCCAUCUUCUUCUAUUUGGUGGAUGCAGAGCAGGGACGGCUGUGUGGAUAUCGGCUUCGAAAGGAUCUCACCACUGAGCUGAGUUGGGAGCUGACCAUUCCCCCAGAAGUACAGCGGAUCGUCAAGGUGAAGGGGAAACGCAGCAGUGAGCACGUUCAUUCCCAGGGCCGUGUGAUGGGGGACCGCAGUGUGCUCUACAAGAGCCUGAACCCCAACCUGCUGGCCGUGGUGACAGAGAGCACAGACGCGCACCAUGAGCGCACCUUUAUUGGCAUCUUCCUCAUUGAUGGCGUCACUGGGCGUAUCAUUCACUCCUCUGUGCAGAAGAAAGCCAAAGGCCCUGUCCAUAUCGUGCAUUCAGAGAACUGGGUGGUGUACCAGUACUGGAACACCAAGGCUCGGCGCAACGAGUUUACCGUACUGGAGCUCUAUGAGGGCACUGAGCAAUACAACGCCACCGCCUUCAGCUCCCUGGACCGCCCCCAGCUGCCCCAGGUCCUCCAGCAGUCCUAUAUCUUCCCGUCCUCCAUCAGUGCCAUGGAGGCCACCAUCACCGAACGGGGCAUCACCAGCCGACACCUGCUGAUUGGACUACCUUCUGGAGCAAUUCUUUCCCUUCCUAAGGCUUUGCUGGAUCCCCGCCGCCCCGAGAUCCCAACAGAACAAAGCAGAGAGGAGAACUUAAUCCCGUAUUCUCCAGAUGUACAGAUACACGCAGAGCGAUUCAUCAACUAUAACCAGACAGUUUCUCGAAUGCGAGGUAUCUACACAGCUCCCUCGGGUCUGGAGUCCACUUGUUUGGUUGUGGCCUAUGGUUUGGACAUUUACCAAACUCGAGUCUACCCAUCCAAGCAGUUUGACGUUCUGAAGGAUGACUAUGACUACGUGUUAAUCAGCAGCGUCCUCUUUGGCCUGGUUUUUGCCACCAUGAUCACUAAGAGACUGGCACAGGUGAAGCUCCUGAAUCGGGCCUGGCGAUAAAGAACAAAGACUGUGCCUAAAAGUGGAGAGCCAGGGGAGUGUGGGUCAGAUAAGCAGCUACAGCUGCAGUUUGGUGGAUUGGUGGAGUAUGUGUGUGUGUCAGUGCUCAGCUAAGAACUGUAGGGAAGAUGGAUGACCUUCACGCAGAACUCCUUUUGGGAUAUACAUGAUGCAGAAAGGAUCCUACAUGGAGAGAGACAGAACUCUCUCAGCUGACACUCUCAGAGAUUCCUGAUGGGCUUUCUCUUGAAGUCCAAAGGCGUCUGCAUUGUUUCCUUUCUUUGCCCAUCCAUGAAUGUUCUGUUUUGUUUUUUUUAAUAAGAAUUCCGGCUGAUUUUUGUGAGGCCUGUUUAAAUUGACUUUACUUUGCCUUUUGUGUUUCUCAAUUUUAUCUAGAAAUCUUUCUGACUUUUUCCAUCUCUUGCUUCAAAGUAAGAGGGGAACUCUCCUUGCCGACUCCACCUUAUAGGUACAUUUGGUGUUUUGCACUGGGAAGAAAUAGGAUCCAUCCUUAGCUGAGGCUUGAGGACUGAUCCAGCCUCUCAUGGCUUCCCUCCAAAGUAACUUAGGGUUGAGGGAUCUAUAUGUGAUGUCAAAACUUACUUUAAACCUCUAGUUUCGUGCUGUCAUUUAUUAGGCUGGGCCACCAAAUCUUUGUUUCAAUUUAUCAGAAGCCAAGUGCAUACUAGCGUCUUGUUUGUUGCCCAUUGCCUAUACUUUUCACCUGAGAUGUGUGAGUUGGGGCCUUUUAAAAACUACUGAAUUGUCUGAGCCUUGAAGACAUUUCCAGGGAGAAGAGAUAAUCUCUCAUUUCACCCACAGGCUGGUCUAAUCAUAACCUAGUUAAAGAUGUCCUUGUUUAAGAACCCCAUUAUUUAUUUUUAGUUUUUAAUAUAAAUUAACAUGUGGGUCAUUAUAUUUCUCCUUAAAUGAGGAAAUUUUAAAUUUUAUUGAUCUAACCUUUGAAGCUUUAAAAAAGGAGAAAGAGGGUAGGGGUGGGAAACUGGCAUACUGUGUGUAUAGCACUGCCGAUUGGCUAGGCCACUGUGUCUCUGCUACAAAUUAAAGAAAUCCUAAAAGUUUUCCUUGGUCAUAGAGUUGGGGAAUGACAGAAUUUUUCUUUGUUGUGAAAUGUAUGUACAGAGUAGACCAUCUCUAGCCCUGUGGUGAAAGAGGUACACUCGAAUGUUUGCAUAAAGCAAGUGACAAAUGACACUGUUUAAGUCCUCUUUUGUGUCUUAGAAGAUCAUUUUGAGGCUAUUUUCACAUUAGAGGGGAUAAAAGCAGUGAAGACAUGGAGUAAGUGUAUUUUAUUUUAGUAAGGAAAGGUCAGUUUAAUCAUAUAUGGGUUGGUUAGGUUAUCUAAAAAUUUGUCAUCUUUCUAUGGUCAUAUGCUGAUGGUAGAUUAUGGCAGAGAAGGAAGAGGAAAUGACAACCAUUUUAUUAAUUGUCAGUUUGAUAUUGAGUGACUGAAUGUCUAAGAAUCUCCAGAAAAAAACAGGCAUCUAUCAUCCUGACCCAAGGCAUAUUUUAACAUAACCUGGGAGAAGAGAGUUAAGUACAAGUUAAAAAAAAUUCUGCCCUAGUUUUGAGAAAGCCUGGCUGGAAUUCUGACUGUCUUACAUACAUAUGUGCAAGGUUAGCCUGCAAGAUUCUAGUUUUUAUUUACCAGUGUGCCAGAAUCUGAAACAAGCUACUGGGAGGGAAGGUAUUUGUCCUUUAGUAAAAUUCCCUGUAUUUCAGCUGUAAUCAAAGUUACCUCAAAGCAGGUGCUUUUUUUUUUUUUGAGACAGAAUCUCACUCUGUUGCCCAGGCUGGAGUGCAGUGGCACGAUCUUGGCUCACGGCAACCUCCACCUCACAAGCAGCUGGGACUAUAGGCAUGUGCCACCACGCUCAGCUAAUUUUUUGUAUUUUUAGUAGAGACGGGGUUUCAUUGUGUUGGCCAGGCUGGUCUCGAACUCCUGGCCUCAAGUGAUCUGCUGGCCUUGGCCUCCCAAAGUGCUGGGAUUACAGGUGUGAGCCACCGAGCUUGGCCAAGUGCUUAAAAUAGUUAAUGCUAAUGCCACAGUCCAAUUUAAAUCUUUUCUUAGUUCUCAACUUUCCUUAAUCUUAAAGCAGCAUUCGGUUCUGAGCAGCUACACUCAGUCUCCACUAAUGGCUGCUGAGACUAUGUUUCCUCUCUCAAUUCUCUGAUCUAUUUGCUUUCUUGUCAUUCCUUGUUUUUUGUGUGUAUUCCUUGACUUACCUCUUCUCCUGUCUUCAUUAAUUAGGUUAAUUUUGGGGCCCCAUGGUGUUUCACGUAAAAAGAUUUGGCUGGGCGUGAUGGCUCAUGCCUAUAAUCCCAGCACUUUGGGAGGCCAUAGUGGAGGAUCUCUUGAGCCCAGGAGUUCCAGACCAGCCUGGGCAACAUAGCAAGACUCUAUCUACAAAAAAUAAAAAAAAAUUAGCCGGGCCUGGUGGCAUGUGCCUGUGGUCCUAGCUACUCAGGAGGCUGAGGUAGGAGGAUCACUUGAGCCUGGGAGGUCGAGGCUGCAGUGAGCCAUGAACAUGCUACUGCAUUCCAGCCUGGGCAACAGAGUGAGACCCUGGCUCAAAAACAAAAACAAAAACUAGUUUGUUUUAGUAUUCAUUAAUUACGUAUAUGAGCACUGGUAGUCUAGUGUUUGUUCUUGUAUACAGUGUUUUCUUAAAUGAGAUGAUGCUAUUUAAUUCUGUUACUUGUUUUUUCAACUAAUGGAUCUUUUAAAGUUUUUUAUUUAAAUUUUUUGUGGGUACAUAUUAGGUACAUAUACUUAUGGGGUACAUGAGAUGUUUUUAUAAAGGCUCAGCUAAUGUAUCUUGAAUAUCAUGUAUUCAUAAAGAUGACUGAAAUAGUUUCUGGAACAAAGUCUGAUAGAAAAAAUACUCAAUUCCUAAUUUAAGUGUUAGAGACUUUAAUGUAAGCUAUCUAAUCUGAACUAGUUUCAUUAUUUGUGUGUGGGUACAUGUUAUGUGCUCCGUAAGGCAUCUUUCAAUUUGAAAAUUUCAUAAUUGUAAUUUCACUGCCUUUAUAAAUUGCUUUUUUUUUGGAGGCAGGGUCUCUGUCACCCAGGCUGGAGAGCAGUGGCACAGUCAUAGCUCACUGCAGCCUCGAACACCUGGGCUGAAGUGAUCCUCCCUCCUUAGCCUCCCAAAGUGCCGGGAUUACAGGCAUGAGCUACUGCACCUGGCCCAUAAAUUGUCAUACUUUUAAAGAGCCUAUUACACAAAGUAUCAUCAGAAUCAUCCCAAGACUCAUUUCCUGAUUCCUAAUUAUUUAAAAUUUUGCUUUUAGGCGAGGCAUGGUGGCUCAAGCCUAUAAUCCCAGCACUUUGGGAGGCCAAGGCAGGCAGAUCAUUUGAGGUCAGGAGUUUAAGACCAGCCUGGCCAACAUGGUGAAACCUGAAACCCCAUCUCUACCAAAAAAAUAAAAAAAUUUAGCCAGGUGUGGUGGUGCAUGCCUGUAAUCCCAGCUACUUGGGAGGCUGAGGCAGGAGAAUCGAACCCAGGAGGCAAAGGCUGCAGUAAGCCGAGAUCAUGCCUCUGCACUCCAGUCUGGGCAACACAGUGAGACCCUGUCUCAAAAAUAAAUAAAAUGAAAAAAUUGCUUUUAAAUCAUGAAA